GUUGCUGCGCCGCCACCGCCCGAGUCAUGUUCCGCGAUCUUCUCAGGCUCUCCUAGCAGCAUCCAUCGCCGCCACCCUAUCUUCACUGGCUUCAUUCACCUUCUCCUUCUCUCUUCGUUGCUGAGCGACAAGCUUCCUAGCGCUAUGACUGUCGUCUCCGUCCCGCAGCGGGAGCCGCUCGUCCUGGGUGGCCGCCUUGCGCCGCUUGGCUUUUCCUCCCGAGGUUACUUUGGGGCCCUCCCGAUGGUGACCACGGCUCCGCCUCCUUUACCCCGGAUCCCGGACCCCCGGGCACUGCCCCCGACCCUCUUCCUCCCUCAUUUCCUAGGGGGAGAUGGCCCGUGUCUGACCCCCCAGCCUCGCGCUCCAGCAGCUCUGCCCAACCGCAGCCUCGCCGUGGCGGGAGGCACUCCUCGGGCAGCGCCGAAGAAGCGGCGAAAGAAGAAGGUGCGGGCCAGCCCCGCAGGGCAGCUGCCCAGCCGCUUCCACCAGUACCAGCAGCACCGGCCGAGUCUGGAGGGCGGCCGGAGCCCCGCGACCGGCCCGAGCGGAGCGCAGGAGGUCCCGGGCCCGGCCGCCGCCUUGGCCCCGAGUCCUGCAGCCGCAGCCGGCACGGAGGGAGCCAGCCCCGACCUUGCCCCGCUGCGGCCCGCGGCUCCCGGCCAAACCCCCCUCAGGAAAGAGGUUUUAAAAUCAAAGAUGGGAAAAUCGGAGAAAAUUGCCCUUCCCCAUGGCCAGCUUGUUCAUGGUAUACACUUGUAUGAGCAACCAAAGAUAAACAGACAGAAAAGCAAAUAUAACUUGCCACUAACCAAGAUCACCUCUGCAAAAAGAAAUGAAAACAACUUUUGGCAGGAUUCUGUUUCAUCUGACAGAAUUCAGAAGCAGGAAAAAAAGCCUUUUAAAAAUACCGAGAACAUUAAAAAUUCGCAUUUGAAGAAAUCAGCAUUUCUAACUGAAGUGAGCCAAAAGGAAAAUUAUGCUGGGGCAAAGUUUAGUGAUCCACCUUCUCCUAGUGUUCUUCCAAAGCCUCCUAGUCACUGGAUGGGAAGCACUGUUGAAAAUUCCAACCAAAACAGGGAGCUGAUGGCAGUACACUUAAAAACGCUCCUCAAAGUUCAAACUUAGAUUUCAGAUUUCAGUAUGUGUGUAAAACAUAAUUUUUCCCAUAUCCCUGGACUCUUGAGAAAAUUGGUACAGAAAUGGAAAUUUGCCUUGUUGCAACAUACAAUUGCAAAAGAUGAGUUUAAAAAAUUACAUACAAACAGCUUGUAUUAUAUUUUAUAUUUUGUAAAUACUGUAUACCAUGUAUUAUGUGUAUAUUGUUCAUACUUGAGAGGUAUAUUAUAGUUUUGUUAUGAAAGUAUGUAUUUUGCCCUGCCCACAUUGCAGGUGUUUUGUAUAUAUACAAUGGAUAAAUUUUAAGUGUGUGCUAAGGCACAUGGAAGACCGAUUUUAUUUGCACAAGGUACUGAGAUUUUUUUCAAGAAACAGCUGUCAAAUCUCAAGGUGAAGAUCUAAAUGUGAACAGUUUACUAAUGCACUACUGAAGUUUAAAUCUGUGGCACAAUCAAUGUAAGCAUGGGGUUUGUUUCUCUAAAUUGAUUUGUAAUCUGAAAUUACUGAACAACUCCUAUUCCCAUUUUUGCUAAACUCAAUUUCUGGUUUUGGUAUAUAUCCAUUCCAGCUUAAUGCCUCUAAUUUUAAUGCCAACAAAAUUGGUUGUAAUCAAAUUUUAAAAUAAUAAUAAUUUGGCCCCCCCUUUUAAAAUAGUCUUGACUCUUUGUGUGUGACUGUUUCUCAUGUUUGAAUGUGUGACUAGGAGAUGAUUUUGUGUGGUUGGAUUUUUUUGACUUCUACUUUACUGGCUGAGUGUGAGCCGCCAUGCCUGGCCAUAAUCUACAUUUUCUUACCAGGAGCAGCAUUGAGGUUUUUGAGCAUAGUACUUGACUACUCUAGAGGCUGAGACGGGAGCAUCUCUUGAGCCUGAGAAGUGGAGAUUGCAAUUGAGCUAGGAUCAGGCCACUGCACUCCAGCCUGGGUAACAGACGCUGUCUCAAAAAAAAGGCCAAGAGAAAGUAAGGGAGACAGA